GCAGAGCUUUUGAAAGGCGGCGGGAGGCGGCGAGCGCCAUGGCCAGUCCGGGCUGCCUGCUGUGCGUGCUGGGCCUGCUACUCUGCGGGGCGGCGAGCCUCGAGCUGUCUAGACCCCACGGCGACACCGCCAAGAAGCCCAUCAUCGGAAUAUUAAUGCAAAAAUGCCGUAAUAAAGUCAUGAAAAACUAUGGAAGAUACUAUAUUGCUGCGUCCUAUGUAAAGUACUUGGAGUCUGCAGGUGCGAGAGUUGUACCAGUAAGGCUGGAUCUUACAGAGAAAGACUAUGAAAUACUUUUCAAAUCUAUUAAUGGAAUCCUUUUCCCUGGAGGAAGUGUUGACCUCAGACGCUCAGAUUAUGCUAAAGUGGCCAAAAUAUUUUAUAACUUGUCCAUACAGAGUUUUGAUGAUGGAGACUAUUUUCCUGUGUGGGGCACAUGCCUUGGAUUUGAAGAGCUUUCACUGCUGAUUAGUGGAGAGUGCUUAUUAACUGCCACAGAUACUGUUGACGUGGCAAUGCCGCUGAACUUCACUGGAGGUCAAUUGCACAGCAGAAUGUUCCAGAAUUUUCCUACUGAGUUGUUGCUGUCAUUAGCAGUAGAACCUCUGACUGCCAAUUUCCAUAAGUGGAGCCUCUCCGUGAAGAAUUUUACAAUGAAUGAAAAGUUAAAGAAGUUUUUCAAUGUCUUAACUACAAAUACAGAUGGCAAGAUUGAGUUUAUUUCAACAAUGGAAGGAUAUAAGUAUCCAGUAUAUGGUGUCCAGUGGCAUCCAGAGAAAGCACCUUAUGAGUGGAAGAAUUUGGAUGGCAUUUCCCAUGCACCUAAUGCUGUGAAAACCGCAUUUUAUUUAGCAGAGUUUUUUGUUAAUGAAGCUCGGAAAAACAACCAUCAUUUUAAAUCUGAAUCUGAAGAGGAGAAAGCAUUGAUUUAUCAGUUCAGUCCAAUUUAUACUGGAAAUAUUUCUUCAUUUCAGCAAUGUUACAUAUUUGAUUGAAAGUCUUCAAUUUGUUAACAGAGCAAAUUUGAAUAAUUCCAUGAUUAAACUGUUAGAAUAACUUGCUACUCAUGGCAAGAUUAGGAAGUCACAGAUUCUUUUCUAUAAUGUGCCUGGCUCUGAUUCUUCAUUCUGUAUGUGACUAUUUAUAUAACAUUAGAUAAUUAAAUAGUGAGACAUAAAUAGAGUGUUUUUCAUGGAAAAGCCUUCUUAUAUCUGAAGAUUGAAAAAAAUAAAUUUACUGAAAUACAAA